AUGCAGUGCUGCUCUUCACUGUAGAAAGAGCCUGAGAAUUAUCUUGAACUCCAAAUCCUGUACCUUUUUUCAUCACAGUUGUGUAUGGGUUUUAUCUACUACUAGUUUUUUUCCAAGCCUUUUCACAUCUUGACACAUAGUAAAUUUGACCAAGAAAAGAUGAAAGGAAACAUAAAAGAAUGUGUUCUUGGCUGGAGAUGACCUACUCUUGGGGUCUAGCUGCCCCAAAGACUGAGAGGAUUGUUAACUCUGACACCUAUAACCCAUUCAUGAUUUAGUUGGUAAGCAGAUCUGCCCAUUUCUUUCUUCUUCAUUGCCAGAUCUCAGUUCAUGCACUAGUUAUGCCCUGCUUCCACUUCAUCUAAGAAUAAUUCUGUGUCGCAAUAUACCAUAAUUAUAUAUUAAUCUUCUCAUAUUUGCAUUAGAACUUUAAGAUUAUUGGGCUACUUAAACUUCGUAACUCCCCUCGUUACAUCUUUUUUUUCCCUGAAAACAUUUGUCAUUUCUCUCCCAACCACUGCCUCAUUUUAAUUUACUAUCUCUGCAAUACUUUUUCUUUUCUUUUCCAUUAGAGAUGAUAUGCUGUCUUCUUUAGGAAACUUUACCUAAGUGUAAGUAAGGAAAUGAAUGCUAUCCUCCCUAGUGUUUUUAUUAUGAUAGCUAAAAUGUAACAUAUAAAAAGAAGUGUAUAUAGAAACAAUAUUUUUGUUUUAGUUCUAUGCCAUAUCUCUCUAUAGGUUAUUUUUUAUAUUUUUAAACGUUUAUUUUUUGAAGGUUGGAACCAGAUAUGUGAGUUUAAGGGGCUUUAAACUCUUUUAAAAAUCUUUUUUUUUUAUAUUUCAAAUUCUGUUUUAUUGUAAAAGUUCCUGCAGAACAGAAAAGUUUUAUUUAAAUAGUUUUCUGUUUUCUUGAGCAUUGUGCAGUGUAUUUUUAGUAUACUUAGCAUACUUACUAUUACUUGAUGUUAAUUCAGCCAAUUUUAGGCUGGUGGGGAAGAUGAUUCAUGUACACUAACAGUUAUAAUGCAAAAUAGAAACUAGUAAAAGCCUCAAGGUUAGUUGCCUCUCCUUGUGCUUCCAUAGUAACCCGUGCUUAUUCCUUCAUUGCAACUAUACUGUAUUGUUAUUGCCUCUAUAUUUAUCUCUGAUAGAGUCCAUCAUAAACUAGAACAGUGGUUCUUAAUUGAUGUGGGGGUGGUAAGGAAUGGGGCUUGCGCAUUUUGGAAAACAUCUUCUCAUAUUCUUUUUCAGGUACAUCACUCUCUCCACCACUAUCACUACUGCCCUUCUUCUUUUGAAAACUCCUGUACUCACCUUUAAGCCCUUCAAAAUUAGGGAAGUGUAUCUUAUUUGUCAUUUUAUCUCUAGUGCUUAGCAUUUUUUUUUGGCAUCUGUGCCCAUUAAGGUAGACAGUAACUGUUUAUUUGUUGCAGGAAGGUAAAACUAGGUUGGAGGUGGAGGGAGCACUUCUAACCUGGAAGAAUAUUGAAGACUUCCUUGAAGAAGUGUCAUUUGAGAGGAGCUAUGAAAAGAAAGUAAACUGGUUUUAUGGAAGUAAAUGAGAACAUUGCAGACAAGAGAUUGAAAGGAAACACACUGAAUGAGGAAAAACUAACAUACGGUCAUCAACAUCCUUGUAUAACCUAGUUUUUAAAAAAAUUGGAUUUCAAAGAAAACAAAAUUAUCUUCCUUUCCAAAUCCAAAAAGAUGAAAACGACUGAGAUACUUUCAAAAGACAACCAAGUGAGCAGCACAGACUAAUGAGUAGAAUCAAUAAGAACGUGGUUUUGGCCCUUUUAACGCUGACAAGUUCUGCAUUUCUGCUGUUUCAGUUGUACUACUACAAGCACUAUUUAUCAACAAAGAAUGGAGCUGGUUUGUCAAAAUCCAAAGGAAGCCGAAUUGGAUUUGAUAGCACACAGUGGCGUGCAGUUAAAAAAUUUAUUAUGUUAACAUCCAACCAAAAUGUACCAGUGUUUCUUAUUGAUCCUUUGAUACUGGAAUUGAUUAAUAAGAACUUUGAACAAGUCAAAAAUACUUCUCAUGGCUCUACUUCACAAUGCAAGUUUUUCUGUGUUCCAAGAGACUUUACUGCAUUUGCACUGCAGUAUCACCUAUGGAAGAAUGAGGAAGGCUGGUUUCGGAUAGCUGAGAAUAUGGGAUUUCAGUGCCUAAAGAUUGAGAGUAAAGAUCCCCGGCUAGACGGGAUAGACUCACUCUCUGGAACUGAAAUCCCCCUGCACUAUAUCUGCAAACUGGCCACUCAUGCGAUCCACUUGGUAGUCUUUCAUGAGAGGAGUGGCAACUACCUCUGGCACGGCCACUUGAGACUUAAAGAACACAUUGACAGGAAAUUUGUUCCCUUCCGAAAGUUACAGUUUGGUCGUUAUCCAGGAGCUUUUGACAGGCCAGAGUUACAGCAAGUUACUGUUGAUGGACUGGAAGUUCUCAUUCCAAAGGAUCCAAUGCACUUUGUAGAAGAAGUACCACACUCUAGGUUUAUUGAGUGUAGGUAUAAAGAAGCUCGAGCAUUCUUUCAGGUAGAAGACAGCUUGGAACUAUCCUUCCAGGGAAAAGAUGAUGUAAAACUUGAUGUUUUUUUCUUCUAUGAAGAAACUGAUCACAUGUGGAAUGGAGGCACUCAGGCCAAAACAGGAAAAAAAUUCAAAUACCUGUUUCCGAAGUUUACACUGUGCUGGACUGAGUUUGUAGACAUGAAGGUCCAUGUACCCUGUGAAACCCUCGAAUACAUUGAAGCCAACUAUGGUAAGACCUGGAAGAUUCCUGUAAAGACGUGGGACUGGAAGCGCUCUCCUCCCAAUGUGCAACCCAAUGGAAUCUGGCCUAUUUCUGAGUGGGAUGAGGUUAUCCAGUUAUAUUGAGAUAGUAGGUUGAAAUGGGAGAAUUUCUCUUUUGGAAAAAAAGGUAGAUAACUGUUUAAAAAAUACAUGUCUAUUUGUCAAACAUAAGUGGGAACCAAAGAAAAAAUGUGACAAGUUUGAAGACACAGAAAGAGUCAUCUGAUGUAAUUCUCUCACUUAGUACUGAGGAAUUUUCAUGUGCCACAUACAAUGCUAGGUUACAGUGGAGAAGCCUAGAUGAAUGAGACAAAUACCUACUUCUUUUAUUCCUCCUUUUGGUAAACAACUCAAUUUUCCUUUGAGGGAACCCUCCCCCACCCUUUGAAGAGUUCAAGUUCUGUACAGGUUUUUAAAACGUGAAGUAAUGUUUGAACUGGAAGAUGAGCUCACCAGGCAAAGCUAAGGAAGGAUAUACUAGUUGAAAAGAAUAACCCACUCCUCUUCUGGGCAUUUAAGCUGGUAUGUUAGUGCUACUUUUAAGAUUGUGGAGUCUGAGUUAAUAUUCAAGUGAUCAGACUUUGAGUGACAUCAAGAAAAGAUGAUAUCAGGUUCAUUUUUCAACUAAUCUUAUGUGGAAUUGAAUUAGAGAACAAGGCAUUAUUCUUUUAGGGAAGGUGAGAGCUUAUUUGUAUCAGAGCUUAUUACUUGUCAGGAUAAGUAAAUUUCUGUACAUGUACUGUUUUCAUAUGUGAAGUGAGAAGAAACUUUAUGCUUGUUUAAUGCUUAAAUUUCCAUCCAUUGUGAGAAUAUUUUCACUGACCUCUGAUGGCACUUGUUGACAAAUCAUUCAAGUGAGACCAUGUUACUAGACAUGAUCUUGAAAGAGGCCAUGAUUUCACAAAACUCAUUUUUAUUUUAUUCUCAGACAGUCUGUUAGGUAAAAAUAUGAGAAAUUCAUGUACAUUUUAUAUUUUCUGAAUUUAUAAUCUGUGCACUCCCAAUUUUAAUGACACUAAAAUAUUAAUAGAAUUUUUUAAAUAUACUCUAAUUUUUAAAACAUACUCUUUAUUAUCUUCAUUUAUCAAUUACAGCUUCGUAUCUCUAAUUUAUGGUCUAUAUACCAAUUUAAAUGGCAUGUAAACCUGCCUGUUUCUUCUCCUCUUCUAAUAUAUCAGAUCUCCAAAAUGGAAGCUAAAUGGUGGACUUGACAACUAUUCACCCUACCUCAGAUCAUAGAGUUUGUAAAGUUUGUGUCCCUCCCCAGUUUUUCAGUCUGUUGAAUGUCGAUGGGGCAAGAACUCAGACUUCUACUUUACCAAGUACCACACACUCUGGAAUGCUUUAGUUUCCUUUUCCCCUCAAGAUGUCUGAGUCAGCUAGGAUGCUGUUUACCCCAUCUCUCUCUUAUAUCACUUGAAUGAUAUAUUGUAAGUGAGAGGUAAAGGAAAAUGUAGGCACAAUAAGCACUGCUAUUUUUCUCUUUGUCUAGGAAAGGAAGCUGAAUCUUAUAUCUUAUCUAUGCUAUUUAGGACUACUUUCUGGAGCUUGGCAGAUUUUCCUCUGACACCAGAGAACAAUAGUAGUCUCAAGAAUGGAAACCUGAAUGUCUGAGGGAAUGGGCUGGUAGACUUUUUCGAAAACAAAUUAGAGAAAGUAACUUACAACCACCCAUUCCGGAUUUGUAAAGCAACAUGAAAACCUUUGAUAAAUGAUAACCAACAGUCUUCUGUCCUAAUUUGCAUUCUCAAUGCAGAAUUAUUGGGUCUUUCAUAAAUAACAUGAGUGGUUUCUGGAGACAUUUAAGAUUGUCAGCAAACUUGUCCCAAAAUGGCACAUCAUCAUAAUCCAUUUUCUCUUUGCUAGAAAAUCAGCCCAUAGAGUGCAUUCCCAAAUUCUAAAUAGCUGACCCUAAAUUCAUUUUUCAUGCUUAAAAAUAAUAGAACAAAUAAUAAUACUAUUUUUGGGCAAAAUCCACCCUACUUGAUGAGGACCAUUUGCUUGUGCUCAGUAUUUAGAAAUGCAUACACUCCACAUUUCUCCCCAUUUCCAAUUGGGACUCCCAUUCUUUGCCAGGAGAUCUUACCCAUCCCUUUUCAGAUUAAUCUUUUAUCCUUUCCUGAAGUACAAAGUCUUAAGAGUGUCUGAAAUCCAAGACAUCUUGGCCCAAUUGACACAGGUUCUAUAUUCUUCCCUACAUAGACCACUGGCUGCUGAAAUACUUUUCUUGUCUUCUGGUUUCACAGGCUUCAGCUCAUGGGUUCCACCCUAACUUGGGGAAACAAAAGCCUUCUCUAGAAUCUGAAGGCCAGGCUUACCUCUGAUUCUGAUUCAUCCAUACUUCAUCUUAUGUAUUUUAACAGUUGGGUUCUGUGGAGUGUCCAGAGACCUUGGGUUAGGUAUAUCCAUCUUCAGUACCUCAUUGGAUCACUUUUCUUUCAUCACUUGAGUAUUCUAGCAGUCAUUCUCCUAAUCUGACCACUUUCAGGUUUAGUUUACCUGGCUUACCUGGGGAAGUUGACAACUUGUUGGUAGUUAGGCACCCAUGAAUGUCUCCAGAGACAUCCUGAGAGGCAAGAUUCCUCUUAAUUGAUAACCAGGACAACCAGGUAGUCACCCAGUCCUCUCUAAGCAGGGAGCACUUGUCCUUCUCUCCUCUGCUGCAGCUACUGAUAUCUGGCCCCUGGAAUAAAACCAUAGUUCCUAAAAUUGAGCAUCCCUAAGAGUAGCUGCUUGGUGGGACAGCUGAUUUCUUUGAUUCCCUAGCUGCAAAACCUGAAAUUGACCACUAGGUGACAGAAUGUUUGCCAGUAUCCCCACAAAACAAGUUAAAACUUAAGUGAAAAUCAUUCUGCUUUUGAAUCUUAAAAGCUAGAAAAACCAUAAUGUAAUAUUCUUUUUAAACCCUCUUAUUUUAUAACUAAAUAAAUAAUCACAGAAAAGAAUGAUCUGAACAAGAACAGCUGAGGCUAAAACCCAAGACUGCCGUGACUCCUAGUCCAAUGUCUGUUUCGCAUCACAACACAGUAUCUUUAACAGUGCUUGAGAUGCUUAACAGAGAAGGCAUCCAGUGCUUCAUUGAGGCUAAGUCUCAGGGUGUUUCUGCCGCUUAGUAUCUUUUUGUUCAGAUUGAGAACCUAAGGCGACAGAGAGGUCAAGGGGAAGUAUUUUCUAGUUCAGAAUUCAGAAUUCUUAGGCAACCUUCAUACCUUUAUCUGGAAAAUGCCUUCUCUCCAGACAAUAAGACAGUUCACAUCUGGAGACAUCAGCCUUUGGUACCUAAUUCUCUAAGCUCAAGAUGCAUCCCAUUGCCACUUUACCAUUCUAUUUCCCAAGGGAACCAUCAGCACCAACCUGCUAAAUGCCUGUAUUUGAAGUCUCUCCCCUUCCUGAAGUGACCUUUUAUGAGGCUCUUUCCUUCCUAAGGGACCUUUCCCUGGUAGUAGUGGUCUCAUUCACAAAAAAGAAUAAUAGAUGUAACUGGAGUCACUUUGCAGUUUUCAAGAUUUUUUUUUUAUCUGCUUGGCUGGAAAGGAGACUAGAGUAUCUAGUUUUUAGUAUUUAAACUACUUUUAAUUAUUUAUAUUGAUACUCUCUGAUAAAUGCAGGUAGUUAAGAAUAGAUUGUACUCAUUCCUUUUUGAGUUUGUGACCUCAAACCAUUGUUUUUAUUCUUACACGACUACAGUACUUCAAAUGGCACAUAGAUAGGCAGGAUAUUACAUAGGUAAGCAGGAAUUUAUACAUUGGGUACCAGAGCUAAAUCUGGAAAACACAUUUGGAAUGAGCUUCCACACUUCAGUCUAAAAUCUCACCCAAACUUAUGGCUACAUAUUUUUCUAAGUUUCCCCCCUAGUUUCACUUUCUGGAAAGUGAACAGUUUUUUAAAUCCUAAAUGUUAUAAAUCCUUAGGAGAAAUAUUCCCUCAAAACCUAGUCAAGAAAGUGCCACAUUCCCACCUUCUAACAGGUAAUUAUUAGUUGUAAUAGCUUUAAUGCAUGGAAAAACUUCAGUUACUGACCAGUCAAGAGAAUUUCUCAAGAAAAAUCCCAGCAACGUUCCCUCUUUCCUCCUUGUCUUCCACUAUCAUUAAGACCUGGGCUAGAUCACCUCUAACAUCUCACUCAGGGAAGGCAAUGUGUUGCCAUAAAAAGACCACAAGCUUUUGAGUUAGGCCUGAAUUUGAAUUUCAGCUUAAUCAUGUGGGAUUUAUGGUGGGGGCCCUUUCAGUCUCAAUUUCCACAUUAGUGAACUGGGGAAAUGAUACAUACUUCUAAGGGUUUUUAGGGGGAUUAAAUGAAGUAUACAGUUCUUAGCCUCAGGCCUAGGAUUAAGUAAGUACUCAAGAAAUGUGCAAUUUUCUAGUUCCAUGUUUCUUUUCUAAUCUUCAAAUGGAAUUAUAGAAACCAUGGGUCAGAACAUAUUCCUUUACUCAAAAGAUUGCAUGACUGAAUUUGCUUAAGAAAAAAAAAAUUGUAUCAAGUCAUUAAUACAAUUAUACAUUAAUUAUAUUACAUUAAUACAAUAUAUGGUUUGUGAAUUCAGAGACAUUACCAGUUUGCCUCCUUCUCUCAAUAGAACUUGUAUUUUCAUUUUCUUGGUUAAGCAGUUGUCUCCUAAUAUUAUCCCAUAUGCUACCUAGUUUGCUGGUCCCAAGCAGUUUACUGUACUUCACUAGAUUUGGUACCUGCUCUCCCCUGGACUUCUUUUUCAAUAUUCUAGCCUUUCCUAGAUGUAAAUCUUUACCUCCUUGUUAGUGAAAUUAGAUAUAAGCCAUGAUUUGGAGAGGGAAGAAAUCUGGAAUACUUAAUUUCAUUUAAUUAUCUAUGCUGAUGAAUGCCUGUAUCAUUGUUAAUAAAGGAGAAUUGAAAAUACUCAUUUCUACUUUCUGCCCUCAAAUUUCUGUUUCUAUCUCAACUAGGCAAGAAUCAGCAGGGUGCAUGAUGCCAUUUUAAGCUGCUUCACAUCAGACUGAAAUCCUAAUUACAGUUCAUAAGUGAAACAGACUAAUUCAAUGGCAAUACCUUUUGUAUAGGUCCUGUGCUUAAAGGAGGCAAGUAUAAAUUUUCUAAUAAGAAAUCCCUGCUUCUUUUGGGUGCAGUGGCUCACACCUGUAAUACCAGCAGUUUGAGAAGCUAAGGCAGGUGGAUCACUUGAGGCCAGGAGUUCGAGACCAGCCUGGCCAACAUAGUGAAACCCCGUCUCUUCUAAAAAUACAAAAAAAUUAGCUGGGCAUGGUGGUGCACGCCUAUAGUCCCAGCUACACAGGAGGCUGAGGCAGGAGAAUCACUUGAACCCGGGAAGCAGAGUCUGCAGUGAGCCAAGAUCGCGGCAUUGCACUUCAGCCUGGGCGAUAGAGCAAGACUCUGUCUCAGAAAAAAAAAAAAAGGAAAGAAAGAAAUCUCUGCUUCCGUACUAUCAAAACUUCUACCCUAGAAUACCCCCUGGCACCUUCUAACCCAACCUAAUACAGAGAUUUUGUAGGGACCCAUUAACAAGCUCCUAUAUAAUUAUAAGCAGCUCUCACAGUAGGGUUGAAAGAGAAUAUAAGGAAAAUUAGAAGUACUGUAUUUUUGCUAUUGGAAAUGAAAUAUUGUUUCAUGCACCUUUGAAAAAAAUAACAGGAUUUUACAGCCUUCUGAUGAUUCAUUCAAAGCAUGGGGAAUAGUUCAUAUGUUUGUUAAAUGAAAAUCUUAUGUAGCUAUUUGUGUGUCCCUCCCACUUCAUAACUACAAAAACAUAUAUAUGAAUUUCUAAACAAAGUGAUAUUUUAAAGAUGAAUUGAUUCAAUGUGUACUUACCAGUUUACUGUGUGGUUUUAUCUUCAGGUACAGAUAGUUUGUGGUACUACUUGAAAAUACCUUUAAUAUUAUUUUCAUCAGAAUUUGUAAUAUAUAAUCCAGUUUGGGAUGAUGAAUAAAAUUUUUCUAAUCUCUUGA